GCGGUACGGGAAGACAGCUUUGGGAUGUCGGAAGAUCCUAGAGGUCCCAAGGUAGCUGACUUGCGAAGCUGAGGCUCCAGCCGAGGGCUCCAGGCCUCUGACCGGCCCAGCAGUGAGCGCGGCUGCCCGACGCUUCAGGGCCGGGAGCAGGGAGCGUGAGUCGCCAUGGCGACGCCGGCGGGUCUGGAGCGCUGGGUUCAGGACGAGCUGCACUCGGUGUUGGGGCUGAGCGAGCGGCACGUCGCCCAGUUUCUGAUCGGUACCGCACAGCGCUGCACCUCUGCCGAGGAGUUCGUGCAGCGCCUACGAGACACUGAUACCUUGGAUCUCAGUGGGCCGGCCCGGGACUUCGCCCUGAGACUCUGGAACAAGGUACCACGAAAGGCAGUGGUAGAAAAGCCAGCUCGGGCAGCAGAGCGAGAGGCCCGGGCCCUGCUGGAGAAGAACCGAUCUUAUAGGUUACUGGAAGACAGUGAAGAGAGCAGUGAGGAGACUGUGAGUAGGGCUGGAAGCAGCCUCCAGAAGAAACGUAAAAAGCGGAAACACCUCAGGAAGAAGCGUGAGGAAGAAGAGGAGGAAGAGGCUUCUGAGAAAGGGAAGAAGAAAACAGGGGGGAGUAAACAGCAGACAGAGAAGCCAGAGUCGGAAGAUGAGUGGGAACGGACAGAGCGUGAACGCCUUCAGGACCUGGAGGAGCGUGAUGCCUUUGCUGAGCGGGUUCGACAGCGGGACAAGGAUCGGACUCGAAAUGUCCUGGAACGGUCAGACAAGAAGGCUUAUGAAGAGGCUCAGAAGCGCCUCAAGAUGGCCGAGGAAGACCGGAAGGCCAUGGUCCCUGAGCUGCGGAAGAAAUCUCGCCGAGAGUACCUGGCUAAGCGGGAGCGAGAGAAGCUUGAGGACCUGGAGGCGGAGCUGGCUGAUGAGGAGUUCCUUUUUGGGGACGUGGAGCUGAGCCGGCACGAGCGGCAGGAGCUCAAAUAUAAGCGGCGAGUGCGGGAUCUCGCCCGGGAGUACCGGGCAGCUGGGGAGCAGGAGAAGCUGGAGGCCACCAAUCGCUACCACAUGCCCAAGGAAACCCGAGGACAGCCAGCCCGAGCUGUGGAUCUAGUGGAGGAGGAAUCAGGAGCCCCUGGGGAGGAGCAGCGGCGCUGGGAGGAGGCGCGGCUUGGGGCAGCGUCCCUGAAGUUUGGGGCCCGAGAUGCUGCCUCUCAGGAGCCCAAGUAUCAACUGGUGCUGGAGGAGGAGGAGACCAUUGAGUUUGUCCGGGCCACUCAGCUCCAGGGUGAUGAGGAGCCGUCAGCUCCACCCACUUCAACUCAGGCCCAGCAGAAAGAGUCCAUCCAGGCCGUCCGCCGCAGCCUCCCGGUGUUCCCAUUUCGAGAGGAGCUCCUGGCUGCUAUUGCAAAUCACCAAGUCCUCAUCAUUGAAGGCGAGACAGGCUCAGGGAAGACCACCCAGAUCCCGCAGUAUCUCUUUGAGGAGGGUUAUACAAACAAGGGUAUGAAGAUUGCCUGCACCCAACCCCGGAGAGUGGCUGCCAUGAGUGUGGCCGCCCGAGUGGCCCGGGAGAUGGGUGUGAAGCUUGGGAAUGAGGUUGGCUACAGCAUCCGCUUUGAGGACUGCACAUCAGAGCGAACUGUCCUCCGCUACAUGACAGAUGGGAUGCUUCUCCGGGAGUUCCUCUCUGAGCCUGACCUGGCGAGUUACAGGGUUUAGAAAACAACCAGGAUAGCAGAGCAUUGCUGCCGAGACUUGAAAUACCGUGUGAAGACCAUUUGAAAACACUUGGAAUGCUCAGCUCAGAGGGAGAAACAGGAAGCAUCCUGGUUCCCUCUAAAUAUGUGAAGGCUGUUACAUGGAAAGAAGGAUCAGAUUGUUUUAUGUGACCCUACACGACAUAGCUAGGAGCCAUGGGGAGGUUACAGGGAGACAGAUUCCAACUCAAUACCAAUGGCUGAGUAACCCUCAGAGUGGUGGAGAUUGCAGGGCCUGUCAGAGUGGUUGGACUCUGGGUCUUGGCCCUCCACACAAGUCUUGGGUAGCUUGGUCUGUGAAUAAUGAGCUCUUAGUGCUGGAAAUGGCCAAGCAGGGGUUGGUUGAACAUGUGUUGAGGGGGAAAAGGGAUUCAUGAAUGUAAUGGGGGUGGGGUCAGGCCAGCUGAACAAUAUGUGCCUUUUUGACUCUUCAGAGGCUGUGAAUUUCUGGUCUUGGAAGAUCACAGUGGAGCAAUUGGACAGAUAGGAUUUUAUCCUUCAUAUCCCUUGCAAAAGAUCUCUAAGAACCCAUGGAGAGCCAGCCAGCGCAAGAGUGUCUGAUGCAGAUGUUUUUGCCCAUCGAGCCAGCCUGCUUUGUGGAAUGGCUGGGGACUUCACCAUCACAGUUAGGCGUGGUGAUGGUGGAUGAGGCACACGAAAGGACCCUACACACAGACAUUCUCUUUGGAUUGAUCAAGGAUGUUGCUCGCUUCCGACCUGAGCUCAAGGUCCUGGUGGCUUCAGCCACAAUGGACACUGCCCGUUUUUCCACCUUCUUUGAUGACGCCCCUGUGUUUCGAAUCCCCGGACGCAGGUUUCCUGUGGACAUCUUCUACACCAAGGCUCCAGAGGCUGACUACUUGGAAGCUUGUGUAGUAUCUGUGUUGCAGAUCCAUGUGACCCAGCCCCCUGGGGAUAUCCUGGUGUUCCUGACAGGACAGGAGGAGAUUGAGGCUGCCUGUGAGAUGCUCCAGGAUCGCUGCCGCCGCCUGGGCUCCAAAAUCCGGGAGCUCCUGGUGCUGCCCAUUUAUGCCAAUCUGCCCUCUGACAUGCAGGCCCGUAUCUUCCAGCCCACACCACCUGGGGCACGAAAGGUCGUUGGAGAAACCCACACU